AGUCAGCACCCGCUGCGCCUGUCCCCGGCUCGUCCAGAGCCUUCCACCCCCUGCCGCCUUCCUUCCCCAAGCCACCCCCAACCUCUCCUAAGAGGCGCCGCCCCAGUCCCGGCCGCCGAACACUCCCUCGCCCAGCAUUCCCCUCCCCCGCCGCCCCCCAGCCCCCGCUGACGCCACAAAGUCCCUAGGCCUCCCGACCCCAGGUCCCCACGCCCCGGGCCGGGCCGCAGCCUCCUGGGCUUCGUGGGGGCAGACCCAGCCUUUCCCGGCAGCGAGCGCUCGGCCAGGUGCACUAGGCGCUGUGCGGGCCCCCCUUCCCCGCGGUGAGUAGCCCCCACCCCGCCGCCUAGGCUACCCUCCUGUGGCGCCUGGGCCACGACCUAAGCCUAACCCGGUCCUCCUCGCCCUCCAACGCCCGGCCUUCCCGCCUCCGCCGGCCGCCGCGUCCCUGGAGGGGCUAGCGCGCUUCAACAAGGUAACUCUACCGGGACCCUAGCGGACCAGAGCGGGAAGGACAGCCAUCCCGGCAGCCAGAGCCAGAGCCCCAGGCCCGCUGCCGCUGUCCCUGCCCGGCUUCGGUCAGGGUGGGCUGGGUGCCUCCGUUAGGGCUCUUGGGGGGAGUCGGAGGGCUGGCGCCGGGUGGUUGGCGUGCAGAAAGCUCCGAGAAACUGGACGUGGGACAGAGCCGGGGAAGUCUGAGACCCCUAGACGCCCUCGCUUUAGGGGAUGGCAGAACGGAAGGGGAGAAUCGUGCUUGCAGUGUAGACGCGAUUUUCAACUCCUUCUGCAACUCGGUCCCCAUAGCAACCCCGUGGCGUAGGCGAAAGUCUGUAGAUCUCCACUGCGUGGGGUCGCGAGUGUUGAGAUUGCAGGGGGCAUCUAUGUGCAUGCUUGUGUGCCUGUGCGUGUGUGCGCGCGUGUACCUGUGUGUACAUGCAUGUAUGUUUACCGAUAUGUGCAUCUGUGCCUGUGUGUGCUGUGUUUGUGGAUCAGUGUUUCUGUGCGUACAUGUUUGUAUUUGUGUGGUGUGUAUGCGUGGGUAUGCGUGUGUGCACAUGCACGUUUGUAUACAUACAUGGGUAUGUGUAUGGGUGUUCGUCUGUGCGUACAUGCACACGCGUGUUUUUUCUGAACCCCACCUCACUACCGAAUGGAAGAGAGCUUUUUUCCUCUGAUAGCCCAUCCCUUCUUCCUUUGGUGUACGGGGUUUUGUUAAAGAAAAAAUUCUGACAUUUGAAAGGCUCUUUAGUCAGGCUACUUGCAAUGGGAGAGUUGCGCCAGCAAAGACAGCUGGGGAUGUAUGGGGGAGUUGGAGUGGGGAUCUGGGUGGGGUCAGUGGAUGGAAAGUGAUUAAGGGAAGGCUCCAAGGGUAGGGGCUUCUCCCUAAGCUGACCUAGCAGGCUUCUCCAGAAAGGCAGGUUGAAGGCCUAGCCGGCAACGGUCUGUCGGGGAGGAGGAGCUGAUGAGAUGUGGAGCUGGGGGUAGCCAGCAGCAGGCGGAAGUGGACGGGUAGGGUCCAGGCCCAGUGGAGAGGAGAGGCGGAGGGGCCUGCAGAGCAUUGGUCAGGGAGGGUCUGUGUAGUUUCUGGGGAGGCAUCUGUGUCUGUUGUUGACAAGGCUAAAAAUGAUGACUCUGGACUCUCUAACUGGACUGCAGUCCUAGCCCUCCUCUGUAAAGGGAGGCUGUACAGGACGGUUGCACACUGCCGGCGCCCAGAUCAUCGGGCUGCUCCCUCCAACUCUCUCCAGAGUCCCUCAAGCGGGAACCUGCCUCGUGUCUCCCAGGAGCCAUGGAGGCUGUGGAACUCGCCAGAAAACUGCAGGAGGAAGCUACGUGCUCCAUCUGUCUGGAUUACUUCACAGACCCUGUGAUGACCACCUGUGGCCACAACUUCUGCCGAGCCUGCAUCCAGCUGAGCUGGGAAAAGGCGAGGGGCAAGAAGGGGAGGCGGAAGCGGAAGGGCUCCUUCCCCUGCCCCGAGUGCAGAGAGAUGUCCCCGCAGAGGAACCUGCUGCCCAACCGGCUGCUGACCAAGGUGGCCGAGAUGGCGCAGCAGCAUCCUGGUCUGCAGAAGCAAGACCUGUGCCAGGAGCACCACGAGCCCCUCAAGCUUUUCUGCCAGAAGGACCAGAGCCCCAUCUGUGUGGUGUGCAGGGAGUCCCGGGAGCACCGGCUGCACAGGGUGCUGCCCGCCGAGGAGGCAGUGCAGGGGUACAAGUUGAAGCUGGAGGAGGACAUGGAGUACCUUCGGGAGCAGAUCACCAGGACAGGGAAUCUGCAGGCCAGGGAGGAGCAGAGCUUAGCCGAGUGGCAGGGCAAGGUGAAGGAGCGGAGAGAACGCAUUGUGCUGGAGUUUGAGAAGAUGAACCUCUACCUGGUGGAAGAAGAGCAGAGGCUCCUCCAGGCUCUGGAGACGGAAGAAGAGGAGACUGCCAGCAGGCUCCGGGAGAGCGUGGCCUGCCUGGACCGGCAGGGUCACUCUCUGGAGCUGCUGCUGCUGCAGCUGGAGGAGCGGAGCACACAGGGGCCCCUCCAGAUGCUGCAGGACAUGAAGGAACCCCUGAGCAGAACAACGUGAGUGUGCAGUGCCCAGAGGUUGCCCCCCCAACCAGACCCAGGACUGUGUGCAGAGUUCCCGGACAGAUUGAAGUGCUAAGAGGCUUUCUAGGUAAGUGGGCACCCAGGGCCAGGACCUCUGACCCAGGAUCUCUUGGCGAUGCCCCACUGUACCCCCUAGCCUCGGAAGCCACCAAUGGGGGGGGUUCUACAAGUGCACUGCCUGGUGACGGUCACUGGCUAUUCACUGUGCCUUCGUAGGGCGGCGUUACUGGUGGUUCUAAUUCAUGGGAUGAAUCUUGUUGAGUUCCCAGUGGUCUCUCUGCCCAGCCCCCUGUACCUUAUUGCCACCAAGGCCCACACACAAUUGGUGUGUGGAAGCAUCAAGUAACCCCAGAUUCACAGCAGGGGAGGCCUCUGCGGAGUUAGGGGACCAUUGGCCACAUCCACCACUAGGGCCCGGGGACUCCCACCUUUGACCCUGAAUGCCCCACACCUCUCCCCAUCUCUCCACCACCACGCCCAUCUACAGAGGAUGUGGUGCCUGAUGCCACCUCCGCGUACCCCUACCUCCUCCUGUAUGAGAGCCGCCAGAGGCGCUACCUCGGCUCUUCGCCGGAGGGCAGUGGGUUCUGCAGCAAGGACCGAUUUGUGGCUUACCCCUGUGCUGUGGGCCAGACGGCCUUCUCCUCUGGGAGGCACUACUGGGAGGUGGGCAUGAACAUCACCGGGGACGCGUUGUGGGCCCUGGGUGUGUGCAGGGACAACGUGAGCCGGAAAGACAGGGUCCCCAAGUGCCCCGAAAACGGCUUCUGGGUGGUGCAGCUGUCCAAGGGGACCAAGUACUUAUCCACCUUCUCUGCCCUAACCCCGGUCAUGCUGAUGGAGCCUCCCAGCCACAUGGGCAUCUUCCUGGACUUCGAAGCCGGGGAAGUGUCCUUCUACAGUGUAAGCGAUGGGUCCCACCUGCACACCUACUCCCAGGCCACCUUCCCAGGCCCCCUGCAGCCUUUCUUCUGCCUGGGGGCUCCGAAGUCUGGUCAGAUGGUCAUCUCCACAGUGACCAUGUGGGUGAAAGGAUAGACACAGACCGGGGGACUCGGGCACUGCUCCUGGCUCUGCAGAAGGUGUGGGCCUUCUGCUUACUGCAGGCCACCUGCCAGGGUUCUCUGGCAUCACGCUGGCAGCCAUUAGACACACAGGGGGGUUUCUCAAAUUCUAAAUAUAAUUGUGAUUAGAACUGUCAAACAUUAAGAGGGUAUACUGACAGAUGCUUCCUAGAGGAAACUUUUGAAAGCCCCUGCGUUCUGAGUGGACCGAUUUCUAAAUCCAUACCUACACACCAGGAA